GGGGACGCGCCGGCGCUGCGGCGUUGGCGCAGUCGUGGGAACAGCGCGGAGCAGGUAACGGCCCCGCUGCUGCCGUCGUCCCCCUCAGCCGGUUACCCUGUUACAGCCCCAGCUCUGGGCCCUUCCGGACCCUCCUGCUACGCUCUUUCUGGGCUUCCAGUAUCGCCGGUCACUCAGUCCUCGCCCCUGCCUGCCUCGCUGGCGCCCCGCCGUUUCCUCCUCGCGGCACAGUUUGCCAAGGAACAGCUACCCCGGCUCGGCAGUGACCGGGCGCCCCGGCGACACACGUACUCUCAGGCCCGCUGGGCAGGGGGACGGCCUGGGCCGAGUCUGUCAGCACUGCCUUCAAAAUGCACCCAGAAUAGAUUCACAAUUCUACCAUUUCUCUCAACCGCCACUGUCACCACCUUGGUCCAGGCCCCCAUCAUCUGAGAAGCACCAAAAGAGGCAAACUGAGAUGCAGACAAAUGAUCAUCCGUAUGCUGAUCAUUUUGAAUAGUUUUUUAAAAUAUAUUCUUUCUUUAAAAAGAGACCAAAACCUGUCAAAAAAAUACUACCGUGGAAAGCUCAUAAAUACUACAGUGUGAAGAACCCUGUGCUUAUCUUCAGUUUAUCAUCAGACAUCUUAGGGAAGUUUAAUAAAGAACACCAGUGAGGAGAUUGUGGACUGCCUAAUAUAUUUCAUCAGAAGAGAAGGCUGGAGAAUUAAGCAGAUGCAGCAAAAAGCAGAAACUGACUUCAAAAAAAACCCUCUCAGUAGAGAAAGUGAUAUUAGAUUCCUAUUGCAAAGGAUCUAAUGCCAGUUAAAUUCUCUUUUGCUUUCUUGAUAAAACAGGAGAAUUGAGAAUUAAAUGAAAAGGUAAAUCCUUUUAAAGACCUCAGAAGAUGGAUCUGUUUGUUUCAAUCUGCUUUUGAGGUUGUUUGCUAUGUCUUUGGCUGAUCUAACAAAAACAAAUAUAGAUGAGCAUUUCUUCGGCGUGGCAUUAGAAAACAAUAGGAGGUCUGCAGCAUGCAAGAGAAGCCCAGGCACAGGCGAUUUUUCACGGAACAGUAAUGCUUCCAAUAAGAGUGUUGAUUAUAGCAGAUCUCAGUGCUCCUGUGGAAGUUUAAGUUCUCAGUAUGAUUAUUCAGAAGACUUUCUCUGUGAUUGUUCAGAAAAGGCUAUUAAUAGAAAUUAUUUAAAGCAGCCUGUGGUAAAAGAAAAGGAGAAGAAAAAGUAUAAUGUUUCUAAAAUCUCCCAAUCUAAAGUUAACAGGUGGCCUUGUUACAGAGUACCACAAUAUUUGGAUUUCACUGGCUUCUUGCCUUUCAUCUCAGCUGAAGAAUCAGUGUUUGAAUUGCCAGUGAAAUGUAAAUACCUAUCUCAGCACCCCAAGAGGAUGGUCUCCAAGUCUGGCCAGAAGGAAAUAUCAGUUGAAAAAAAGCACACCUGGAAUGCAUCACUCUUUAAUUCUCAAAUCCAUAUGAUUGCCCAAAGAAGAGAUGCUAUGGCUCAUCGAAUACUCUCAGCAAGGCUUCAUAAAAUUAAAGGACUAAAAAAUGAAUUAGCUGAUAUGCAUCAUAAAUUGGAAGCCAUCCUUACAGAAAACCAAUUUUUGAAACAACUUCAGCUUAGGCAUUUGAAAGCUAUAGGAAAAUAUGAGAAUUCACAAAAUAAUCUACCUCAAAUUAUGGCUAAACAUCAGAAUGAAGUAAAAAAUUUAAGGCAACUACUUAGGAAAUCCCAGGAAAAGGAAAGAACUCUAUCUAGGAAACUUAGAGAAACUGACAGCCAGUUACUGAAGACUAAAGAUAUCUUGCAGGCACUGCAGAAACUUUCUGAAGACAAAAACCUUGCAGAAAGGGAAGAACUCACUCAUAAAUUAUCUAUUAUCACAACAAAAAUGGACGCAAAUGACAAAAAAAUACAGAGCUUGGAAAAACAACUGAGGUUGAACUGCAGAGCCUUUAGCCGGCAGCUGGCUAUUGAGACUCGGAAGACUUUAGCAGCUCAGACAGCUACCAAGACUCUGCAGGUGGAAGUAAAACACCUUCAACAAAAACUUAAGGAAAAGGAUCGUGAGCUUGAAAUUAAAAACAUCUAUAGUCAUCGAAUACUUAAAAAUUUACAUGACACAGAGGACUAUCCAAAAGUUUCUUCAACAAAAUCAGUCCAAGCAGACAGAAAAAUUUUGCCAUUCACAAGUAUGAGACACCAGGGAACCCAAAAAUCAGAUGUUCCACCUUUGACAACUAAGGGUAAAAAGGCAACAGGAAACAUCGAUCAUAAAGAAAAAUCAACUGAAAUAAAUCAUGAAAUUCCUCACUGUGUGAAUAAACUACCAAAGCAAGAGGAUUCUAAGAGAAAAUAUGAAGAUUUAUCAGGGGAAGAGAAACAUUUGGAAGUCCAAAUACUGCUGGAGAAUACUGGAAGACAAAAAGACAAAAAAGAAGACCAAGAAAAGAAAAACAUUUUUGUGAAAGAAGAGCAAGAACUACCACCAAAAAUAAUUGAAGUUAUUCAUCCUGAAAGAGAAAGCAAUCAAGAAGAUGUUCUAGUAAGAGAAAAGUUUAAAAGAAGCAUGCAGAGAAAUGGUGUGGAUGACACACUUGGCAAAGGCACUGCUCCCUACACGAAAGGCCCCCUCAGACAAAGAAGACAUUACUCAUUCACAGAAGCAACUGAAAACCUGCAUCAUGGGCUUCCUGCUUCAGGGGGGCCAGCCAAUGCCGGCAACAUGAGGUACAGUCAUAGUACAGGCAAGCAUCUCAGUAACAGAGAGGAAAUGGAGCUAGAGCAUUCUGACAGUGGGUAUGAGCCCUCAUUUGGUAAGUCUUCCAGAAUAAAAGUGAAGGAUACAACUUUCAGAGAUAAGAAAAGCAGUCUCAUGGAAGAACUCUUUGGAUCAGGCUAUGUCUUGAAAACUGACCAAUCAAGUCCUGGUGUUGCAAAAGGCUCAGAGGAGCCUUUGCAAAGUAAGGAGUCGCAUCCCCUGCCUCCCAGUCAGGCCUCCACCAGCCAUGCUUUCGGAGACUCUAAAGUAACUGUGGUAAAUUCUAUUAAGCCAUCGUCACCUACAGAAGGAAAAAGAAAAAUAAUUAUUUAAAUAUAAUCAAUAUCCUAAUGCAUUCUGGUUUGAUAUAAUGCUGCUUAUGUGCCUUGCAUCUUAUUUUUGAAAUGUGUGAGAGAGGGAGUGUAUGUAUGUGUGUGUUUUAGUACUUAAUUGACUUUCGAUAAUUAAAUUUUUGUUUGAUUGCUAA